AUAACUGAAAGUAGCUAAGGCACCCCAGCCGGAGGAAGUGAGCUCUCCUGGGGCGUGGUUGUUCGUGAUCCUUGCAUCUGUUACUUAGGGUCAAGGCUUGGGUCUUGCCCCGCAGACCCUUGGGACGACCCGGCCCCAGCGCAGCUAUGAACCUGGAGCGAGUGUCCAAUGAGGAGAAAUUGAACCUGUGCCGGAAGUACUACCUGGGGGGGUUUGCUUUCCUGCCUUUUCUCUGGUUGGUCAACAUCUUCUGGUUCUUCCGAGAGGCCUUCCUUGUCCCAGCCUACACAGAACAGAGCCAAAUCAAAGGCUAUGUCUGGCGCUCAGCUGUGGGCUUCCUCUUCUGGGUGAUAGUGCUCACCUCCUGGAUCACCAUCUUCCAGAUCUACCGGCCCCGCUGGGGUGCCCUUGGGGACUACCUCUCCUUCACCAUACCCCUGGGCACCCCCUGACAACUUCUGCACAUACUGGGGCCCUGCUUAUUCUCCCAGGACAGGCUCCUUAAAGCAGAGGAGCCUGUCCUGGGAGCCCCUUCUCAAACUCCUAAGACUUGUUUUCAUGUCCCACGUUCUCUGCUGACAUCCCCCAAUAAAGGACCCUAACUUUCGAUACUGACUUCCUGGGAUCUUUUAGAGGUUGAGGCAUAAAUGAUUAUUAAUAUUUAAAAACAUCUGUUGAGAGCUUUGUACGAGGCUUAGUAUUUAGACAUGAUGUACAUUUUUUACAGUGCAUACUACUCAUAAUCUUCUGAACUAGGAACUUUCCUGCUCAGGAAACUAUUAGAUGAGAAACUAAGAAAGGAAUAGUGCUUCCAUUUCUUUUUCUUUUUUCUUUUUUUUUUUUUUUUUUGAGACAGAGUCUUGCUCUGUCAGCCAGGCUGGAGUGCAGUGGUAGGAUCGGCCUAGUGCUUCCAUUUCUAGGGGCUGUUAUCCUGUACUGGUAGUCGUGAAUUCAAAAAUAUAACUUUCCUACUGUGGGCUGCAGUAUUCUCAUCAGAAGUGUAGAUCACGAUGCUACUUCCUGGGAUUUAUCUGGACCAAGACGUGUGACAAAUGGAAGUUUCCCGUUUUCUGAAGGAAGUGUUGUCUGCAAAAAUAAAAAUAGUCAAGAGCUUUCUCAGAGAA